AGAGUGCGCGGGGCGGCGCGCGGCGUGCAGGUCGCAGCUGUGGCUCGGGUGCUGGCAGGUGCUGGCGGGACUGGCGGGGAUCGCCGUGGACUGCCUCAGGGGCGCCGCAGCCCGCUCGGCCCGAGGGCCCGCCUAACCGCGCCGCCCGCGCCCGCUCCUCCUCGGCCCGCGCCCGGAGCGCGGGGGCCGCCGGCGCUGGGUACUCGGCGGCCACCGGGGAUCGGGGCUGAGCGGUCGGUUCCCGCCCCCGUGCCGCCGCCGCCGCCUUCCGGCCGACCGCCCGGCUUGGCCGCUGCUGCCGCGUCUGGCCCCCGGGUCCCCGCCGCUGGGGGCGCGGGCGGGGUCGGGGGUUGCCGGGCGCCGCCCCCCGUGCGCCUGGAGUCCACAUCCCGGGCCCGGCGGCCGGCGAGCAUGGAGGAGAAGUACCUGCCCGAGCUGAUGGCGGAGAAGGACUCCCUGGACCCCUCCUUCACGCACGCCCUGCGCCUGGUGAACCAAGAAAUAGAAAAGUUUCAAAAAGGAGAAGGCAAGGAUGAAGAAAAGUACAUCGAUGUGGUGAUUAAUAAGAACAUGAAGCUGGGACAGAAAGUGUUAAUUCCCGUAAAACAGUUCCCUAAGUUCAACUUUGUGGGGAAACUUUUGGGUCCACGUGGCAAUUCUCUGAAGCGUUUACAAGAAGAAACCUUGACAAAAAUGUCCAUCCUUGGGAAAGGUUCCAUGAGAGACAAGGCCAAGGAAGAAGAGUUGAGGAAAAGUGGAGAAGCGAAGUACUUCCAUCUCAAUGAUGAUCUCCAUGUUCUCAUUGAAGUGUUUGCCCCACCUGCAGAAGCUUAUGCCAGGAUGGGACAUGCUUUGGAAGAAAUCAAAAAGUUCCUCAUCCCUGAUUAUAAUGAUGAGAUCAGGCAAGCACAGCUCCAGGAGUUAACAUAUUUGAAUGGUGGUUCAGAAAAUGCAGAUGUUCCAGUGGUUCGAGGGAAACCCACCUUGCGUACAAGAGGUGUACCAGCCCCAGCAAUAACCAGAAUACCAGCACAGAAUGAAUAUCCCCUCCAGAAUAGAGUGUGGAGAAUCGAGCACAUCCGCUGCUGUUGUUUAGGGGAUACUGUGUUCCUCACACUAGAUCUGCCAUUUUUACUGAAUAUAAUUUAUAAUUCAGUUGUCGGUUUCUAAAUUAAGUUGUUGAAAAUGUUAUGAACAGAGGAGGAAGACAGAAGUAGUUUUUUUGUUUAUUUUGAAUACAGUACCUGGACAGAUACCUCCAUCUGCACAGAUGAAAACUCAUCCCUCGUGAUUACAGCAUAUGCAUUGCUUGUCAUUUAAAGUUGUUUUAAUGUCUUGAUGGUUAAUAUUCUGUGAUAGCAUUAUUUUUAAGUUCAAAUUUUAGACCCUAGUUUCAGUUUGUGGUGGAGUAAUGAUUGGUUCAGUGCCAGAGUUAAAUACCUUUAUUUGCGUACUUACGGUUACCACCUGUGUACUUGAAAUCAUAAGCAGCUCAUAUGCUAGGCACCAGCAGGGCACUGAACACACAACCCACUUUACUUCCUCCAUAUUAUUAUGGUCUUCCUUGGUCCCAAGUCCUUUAAACACCUUGUUUCUACAGUACAAUGUUUAUAUUCAUACGGCAGGAAUUCAAAGCCUUCUUGGUACGUGUUUUCUCAAAUCCUUUGUACAGUUUAGUCUACUGAUUAUUUUGCCAUAUUUCCUGUGUAUUUAACCAACCCUAGGGUAGAAGCUUUGUUUCAUAAAGUUGGUGCUUGUAUUCUUCUAUAUCUUUGCUCACUUGUUUCUUCUGUCUCGCCUUUUCAAAAUCAUUAUUACCUUCAAGUCUGAAUUGAAACUCAUUUUAACAAACACUUAUAUUGCAGCUACUAUUGGUUGAGUACUUUUCUAAGGACUUUACAGAUAUUAACUAAGUUAUGCCUCAUCAUAGUCCGAUGAGGUGGGCACUGUUUUGUUAACAUUACCAUUUUUCAAAUGAGGACAGUGAGACCAGGGAGGUAGAUUCUUUGCCGAAAGUCAUGCAGCUAGUGGUUGGUAGAGCCGGGUGGAAUCCAGGCAGUGUGCUUUCAUAAUCCAAACCUCUCCUCUCUGCUUGGUCCUUCCCUUGUGUUUUGAUCCAGAAUAAGUAAUAAGUUUUUUUUUUUUUCCCAUUCCCUUACUGUAGUUCUCCCAGAUAAUUUUCAUUCUAGCACUUUUAUUGUGUUUUCAUUAUGGCUCAUGAUCACACUUUUAAUACAAGAUGAAAAGACUUAAAUAGUCAUGCACCACAAAAUGACAUUUUUGGUCAAGGACGGACAGAACAUGUAACAGUGGUCUCAUAAGAUUAUGAAAGAACUGAAAAGUCCCCGUUGCCUAGUGACGAUGAUGAUCUUGAUGAUCUUGACCCUAUGUAGUCCUAGGCUAUAGGCUAAUGUGCGUUUGUAUCUUAAUUGCAUACGAAAACAGCUUAAAAAAUAAUUUUAAAAGUUAACAGAAGAGUACUGAUAGGAUAAAGAUAUAAAGAAAAUAUUUUCGUACAGAUUCACAGUGUUUGUGUUUUAAGCCAAGUGUUGCUAGAAAAGAGUCAAAAAGUUUAAAAAAAAAAGUUAAAAGUUGACAAAUUUUAAAAAAUUACAGUAAACUAAGGGUAAUUUUUGAAGAAAGGAAAAUAUUUUUAAAAUAAAUUUAGUGUAGUCCAAGUUUAUAAUGUUUAUAAAGUCUACAGUAGUGUCCUAGGCCUUCACAUUCACUUGUCACUCACUCAGUCACUCACCCAGAACAACUUCCAGUCUUCCAAGUUCCACUCAUGGUAAGUGCCCUAUCUAGGUUUACCAUUCUCCAUCUUUUAUAUUGUCAUGUCUCCAUCUUUUAUUGUGUCUCCACUGUACCUUUUCUGUGUUUAGAUAUGUGUAGAUACACAAACACCUAUCAUUGUGUUAUAGUCACAUACGGUAUUCAGUACAAUAACAUGCUGAACAAGUCUGUAGCCAAGGAACAGUAGGCUGUAUCAUAUAGCCUAGGCGUGUAGUAGGCUACGCCACCUAGGUUUAUGUAAGUACACUCUGUGAUGUUUGUACAAUGACAAAAACACCUAAGGAGCUGUUCCUUAGAAGGUAUCCUCAUAGCUAAGCGACUGUAUUUAUUUACUCCUUUUUUUCAUGAAAUCACAUGCGGUAACUAAUGAUAGGUGGUAACUAAUGCCCAACUAAUAUAGUCCACAGAAUAAAACUAAGGUAAAUAUAAAUUGAUGAGCAAAUUAGGGUAGAAAAUUACAAAAACCCAAGGGUAAGGUCAGUACACAAAAACGUACGUAUUACAACAUUCCGUAGUGUUGGCAGAAUUGGUCUUGAAAUUAUACUUUGAGUUGCCUUGUGGCUAAAGAUGAGGGAAAUAUGGCUACAGAAUUCAGUGUCUAAAUGUCCAAAACCAGUCACAAUACAUACAAAAGAAAAACAUACUUGUUGGAGCCUAUGAAUUUCUACUUAAGACUUGUGAGAAAAAUCUCCAAUGAAUAGCCAUAAAUUGGCCUUCAUAUGAUGUGAUAAUAUCUUCAAUGGCAUUCUUGUUUGCCAUAUUCAGUUCCUUAGUAAGUCAUUUUUCUUUUGCCUUUAAAAUCAACCUGAAGUCAUUUUUUCUUUAAUCAUCUCUGCCAUCCUUCCCAGUCUAAUCCACACUACUCUUCCAUUUUCAGUCACAAUGAUUUUUUCAAAUUAAAUGUGAUCUUAUAUCUUCCAUACUUAAAAUCCUUCAGUGGCUCCUUUCCAGUUAGAAGGGAAUCCACACUUCCUCAUAUGCACUUACAUAAUCCAGCACUUGGCACUCUCCUCCCCUAUCUGACUCUAUCUUAUUCCACUUUUCCAUUGUCUUAACUCCAGCGUUACUGGUCUCCUUUCUGUUGCUCCUUAAAUAGACGAAGCUCAUUUCUUUCCCAGAUCCUUCACAUUUAUUCUCCUUCUCGUUGAAGGCUUUGUCUCCAGGUGUCUGGCCGCCUCCCUCUCAGCAUCGCAUCCUCAGCAUACACGGUCAGAGAAGCCCUUGCCGAGCACGCAGUGUGAAGGGUCCUUCCUCUCAGCCAGAAGCUGGCUCAGAACCCCCUGUCCUGGUGGAGUAGUAUCAUUGGUCAAGCCAAUUUACCUUAUUUAUUCACGUUGUCAUUGGUUAUUCCUUAUGGGUAAUGCAAAUCCAUAAAGACCCAUGUGUCCCUCGUACCUUGCAUAUAGUAAUUGCUCAGUAAACAAUAAUGUGAAUAAAGUGCUGUAGCACAUUCUUUAGCCUCUUUCUGAUCAAGUGUUGACCACUGGAAAUAUUCUUUUGCUAAUGCUGAUCUUAUUUGCCACAGGACUGGGUAUGUGAAGGUACUGGUUUUGUCUGACUCAACAGUUGUGAGCCGUCCAGGAUGCUGCCUUCUGUUCCUCUCCUAACACUCGGUGGCUUCUGUGCUGCUUUUCCAUUGACCUUUGCUCUGGCUCUUCUGGCCCUUUCUUCCACGUAGGAGCAGUCCUACCUUCCCACAUUUGAUACCAGAAGCAGCAAGAAGAAACAUGAACAAAAGAGAUUAUGCCCUCUUUUUAAGUAUUAAGUGCGUGUUCCCAGAUAUUGGUGCUUAAUGUAGUGGUUUUGUUUUAAGUGAGAACAUUAGGCUAACCCAGUCACCCAGGGUCAUUUAUCAGUUUUCAUCGAAUCAGGGAAAUUUUCAGCUACUGUUUCUUCCGAUAUUUUACUUGCCCCUUUCCCUGUUUCCACACUAUGGGAACUGUCAGCUUAAGAUAAUCCUUUAUAGUUUCUUUUGAGCAUUAGAUCAUAUGUUACUGAUUUUCAUGAUGUCACAUCUUUGUGACGCUGGUAUUUUACCAGAUGCUGUGAUAAACAAUAAACAUUAUCUGAAAAUAAGUGUGGAUCAGGAAAUGAGAGUGACAGUGUCCCAUCUGAUCCCAUGGUUUGAGAAGUUACGUAGCACCCAAUAUGCAUAAUUGCUGUUAUUUAAUAAUGAAAUAAAAUAUUUCCUUUCAAUUAUGA